AGUCUGCGCACCGGGCUCGCUGCUGCACCACGCGUCACCCACGCAGACCAUGGCAGCCGCCGACGGUUCGCUCUUCGACAACCCCAGGACGUUCUCCAGACGUCCCCCAGCCCAGGCGAGUCGGGGAUGCGCCUGGAAGCGGGGAGUGGAGCGGUGUGGAGGGGCGGGGAGCUGGCUCCUGCGCCUAGAAAAGUAAAGGAAGGAAUUAGAGGCUGUUUCCCGUGGAAGCAAGCAAAGGCUACGAAAAGAAAAUACCAAGCGUCCAGUGAGGCUCCCCCAGCGAAACGGAGGAACGAAACUUCAUUUCUCCCAGCCAAGAAAACUAGUGUUAAAGAAACUCAGAGGACUUUUAAGGGGAACGCACAAAAAAUGUUUUCUCCAAAGAAGCAUUCGGUUAGCACAAGUGAUAGAAACCAGGAGGAGAGACAGUGCAUUAAGACUUCAUCACUGUUUAAAAACAACCCUGACAUUCCAGAACUCCACAGACCUGUGGUAAAGCAGGUGCAAGAAAAAGUGUUUACUUCAGCUGCUUUUCAUGAGCUGGGCCUCCACCCACAUUUAAUUUCCACAAUAAAUACGGUCUUAAAAAUGUCUAGUAUGACCAGUGUUCAGAAGCAAAGUAUUCCUGUGUUGCUGGAAGGCAGAGAUGCUCUCGUGAGAUCCCAGACGGGCUCAGGUAAAACUCUUGCCUAUUGCAUCCCUGUGGUCCAGUCCCUUCAAGCAAUGGAGUCAAAAAUACAGCGCAGUGAUGGCCCCUAUGCCCUGGUGCUCGUGCCAACGAGAGAGCUAGCUCUACAAAGCUUUGACACUGUCCAGAAACUGCUUAAGCCUUUCACCUGGAUUGUGCCUGGAGUGUUAAUGGGAGGAGAGAAGAGAAAAUCAGAAAAGGCCAGACUCCGCAAAGGAAUAAAUAUCCUUAUCUCAACUCCUGGACGCCUGGUGGAUCAUAUAAAAUCCACAAAGAACAUUCAUUUUAGUCGGCUGCGGUGGUUGGUGUUUGAUGAAGCAGACAGAAUCUUGGAUUUGGGUUUUGAAAAGGACAUCACAGUGAUACUUAAUGCUGUAAAUGCUGAAUGCCAAAAACGACAGAAUGUCUUGCUAUCAGCGACACUCACAGAAGGUGUAACGCGGCUAGCUGAUAUCAGUUUGCAUGAUCCAGUCAGUAUUUCUGUCCUGGACAAGAGCCAUGACCAGUUGAACCCAAAGGACAAAGCGGUCCAGGAGGUCUGUCCUCCACCAGCUGGCGACAAGCUGGACAGCUUUGCAAUACCAGAGAGUCUCAAGCAGCAUGUGACUGUGGUUCCCAGCAAACUGAGGCUUGUCUGCCUAGCGGCCUUCAUCCUUCAGAAAUGCAAGUUUGAGGAAGACCAGAAGAUGGUUGUCUUUUUCUCAAGUUGCGAGCUGGUGGAGUUCCACUACAGCCUCUUCCUACAGACCCUGCUGAGCAGCUCAGGGGCGCCGGCAUCAGGGCAGUUGCCAUCUGCCUCCAUGCGAUUAAAAUUCCUACGGCUGCAUGGCGGCAUGGAGCAGGAGGAAAGAACAGCAGUGUUUCAGGAAUUUUCACAUUCCAGAAGAGGCGUCCUUCUUUGCACGGAUGUUGCAGCUCGGGGCUUAGAUCUCCCUCAAGUCACGUGGAUUGUUCAGUACAACGCUCCAUCUUCACCUGCAGAAUACAUCCACCGGAUUGGAAGAACCGCCCGGAUUGGCUGCCAUGGGAGCAGCCUGCUCAUUUUGGCUCCUUCGGAGGCAGAAUAUGUCAACUCGUUGGCUUCUCACAAAAUCAACGUUUCUGAGAUUAAGAUGGAAGAUAUUUUGUGUGUUCUGACAAGAGAUGAUUGUUUUAAAGGGAAACGAUGGGGAGCCCAGAAAUCCCAUGCUGUUGGCCCCCAGGAAAUCCGAGAGCGAGCCACAGUCUUGCAGACGGUAUUUGAAGAUUACGUGCACUCCAGUGAGAGGAGGGUCUCCUGGGCAAAGAAAGCUCUGCAGUCCUUCAUCCAAGCCUACGCCACCUACCCCAGGGAGCUGAAGCACAUCUUCCACGUCCGAUCCCUCCACCUUGGGCAUGUGGCGAAGAGCUUCGGACUAAGAGAUGCCCCCAGGAAUCUUAGUGCCUUGACUAGAAAGAAGAGGAAAGCACACGUGAAAAGGCCUGACCUUCAUAAGAAGACCCAGAGUAAACACAGCCUCGCUGAAAUCCUACGUUCGGAAUACUCAAGCGGCAUGGAGGCCGACAUCGCCAAGGUCAAAAAGCAAAACGCACCUGGAGAGCCUGGUGGCCGGCCCCUGCAGCACAGUCUGCAGCCGACACCCUGCUUUGGCCGUGGGAAAACAUUAAAAUGGAGAAAAACCCAAAAAGGUGUACAGCGGGACAGCAAGACUUCCCAGAAAGUUUAAAAUCUCUCUGGGUCUUCGAGUGGAACCUGGAAGCCCCGGGUGGCAGUGGAUUGAUGUCCAGUUCUUGUCAGAGGAGGCUUGUGAAAAAUAACUGCGCCUUUGCCUGAAUACCACGUCCCCAAGAAUCAGAGGGGCCACAGCCCUUCUCCUCCAUGGGAGGCCCUGGAGCCUGAUAGAAAUCAGUGGUGUGGGGCACUGUAGAGACUAGCCAGCUCCCGACGGAAGGGGUCUGUGUCUUGUAUUGAUCCCAUCAGUGCCCGGCACUCCCUUCACCCAGGUGCUGACGUGCCGGGGUUGAGCUGGCACCCCGGGAUGUGAUGUAAGAACGCCCUGCGCGUCAGCCUGGAACGGGCUUGAUUGCUGCCCUUAACUGUGUUCUGAAGUUUCACAGCUUGGCUUCAGCCUAUCAGCGCAUACAUUGGCAUGAAUUUUGUGAAUUAGGGUGUUAAAAACUGGAAUUGAAUUUGUACAAAAAGAGAAUAUAUUUAUCACUAAUUAUUUUCUUAAUGUAGGAAUGUACCGUUAAAAAGGACCAAAAGUUUUUGGUCUGGGUCAAAAAAUACGAAUGUGUUCUCAGGCUCGUGGUCCCUCUUAUUUUCUUCUGGAAACACGAGGUUGCAUUUACAUGCAUUGCUCCCUCUUUCAUGUCCACUGAAAACUCACUCUCUCAGGGCUAAUUGAUUUACUGUUGGCUUUUUAUUAUUUGCCUUUGAAGUCAAAAGGCACCAGUAUCCCAAGCUUUUUUUCCCUAUCGAAUCCUGUCUUGUCUUCAAGAAAGGUCUGGGGGUCUUUGUAUUGUGACCCAGGCCACAGCUGCCCGCCCCCCGCCCCCGACCCACCCCGCCCUGCCCCUGCAUUGUGUUUUCUGGGAGGUUUGAAAGAGGCCCCCUGGAGCAUAUUGAUUUCCCAAUAAAUGUAAGAUUUGGGCACUUGCAGAGGGGUCCAGAAGAGAAAGGGUUGGAGGCCUCCACACCUGUGGGCACCGCUCCUGUCCUCUCCACUGUGUCUUGCCUUCUCAGUUUCCUUCUCCUCUGCAGUGACUGUGCCGCCCUCUGUGGUCUCCCCAGGACCAGUGUUGAGGCACCACUUCAGUAGAUCCCCCCAGAUCCUUGGAAGGUCUGAGUGGCCACGAGAGGGUGGUGAGAGUUGGCAAGGUGGGCCUUCCUGCAGGGACCACGGGGGGUCAGCAUCCUUGCCUCCGUUCUAGACACAGGUGAAUGUCAGUGGGCACCCACACUGGCGGAGACUCCAGUGUGAGGGCAAGGAGGAGCCUAGUGAGACUGGAUCCUCUGCAGGUGGAAAAAUAGGACCUUCUCAGAGUUGGCUGUCACAUACAAAUUAACAGGGACUGUGGGUGACGUUUCUAACAAUAAUAAUUAAAAAACAACAACCCUGCAGCACAUGUCAGCCUGGCGUUGGGCAAGUCUGCCACCUUUCUUUUAUUUCGAUGUGUAAUGGUUCACAUGAUUUGGAUGAGAAAAGGAGGGAUCAAACUUUAUAGACAAAACCCAGCUGUGUGAAAAACAGGAUUAAUGCCAGUGAUUGGGGAUGAUCAAAGAGAAACCUUACUUUUUCUCCCCCAGUACUCAUUCCACUAAAGGGCGAAUUGGCAGAGUUCGGCAUCCCUGGGGGGAAAGAGAAGUGCUAGAAUCAUGCAACGUGUGAGUGACGAUAAUUCCAAGAUCAAAACUUACACACUUAAUCUGCUAACUCUUAUGGUGAGGGUUUCUUGCCAUAGAUGCUAUGUGGGUCUGUUUCUAAGUAGAAUCACUAUAUUACCCCAGUUAAUAAAGAAACAUGGAUUUAGCAGAUUUAAGGUUAAUAUUGUUUAAAUUUAAAUAACCUUAAAAUAAAUCUCUUUCUCUUCUA